CUUCUCCUCGUUUCCACCCCUCCCCCCUCGGUCGUGGGCCUCAUUCACGCUUCCCCGGGCUUGGGGAGGGGGCGGAGGCCCGGCGUGACAAGCGGCCCAGACUCCCGUGGGCGCCGCACACCUGUUGUUUGCAGCAGCCAGCGACCCGCACUACCGCUCUCGGCGGGCGGGGAAGCGGCCGCAGCGGAGCCGACCCGGCAGGUGGCCGCGGGCGGGGCCGGCGAGCGAAAGUGCGCGGGGGCCCGACCACCGCGGGGCCGGGACGCGAUGGCGGCGGCAGAGCCCGCGAGCUCGGGCCAGCAGGCGCCGGCAGGGCAGGGGCAGGGCCAGCGGCCGCCGCCGCAGCCUCCGCAGGCGCAAGCCCCGCAGCCGCCCCCGCCGCCGCAGCUCGGGGGCGCCGGGGGCGGCAGCAGCAGGCACGAGAAGAGCCUGGGGCUGCUCACUACCAAGUUCGUGUCGCUGCUGCAGGAGGCCAAGGACGGCGUUCUGGAUCUCAAAGCGGCUGCUGAUACUUUGGCUGUGAGGCAAAAAAGGAGAAUUUAUGAUAUCACCAAUGUCUUAGAGGGAAUUGACUUGAUUGAAAAAAAGUCAAAAAACAGUAUCCAGUGGAAAGGUGUAGGUGCUGGCUGUAAUACUAAAGAAGUCAUAGAUAGAUUAAGAUAUCUUAAAGCUGAAAUUGAAGAUCUAGAACUGAAGGAAAGAGAACUUGAUCAGCAGAAGUUGUGGCUACAGCAAAGCAUCAAAAAUGUGAUGGACGAUUCCAUUAAUAAUAGAUUUUCCUAUGUAACUCAUGAAGACAUCUGUAAUUGCUUUAAUGGUGAUACACUUUUGGCCAUUCAGGCACCUUCUGGUACACAACUGGAGGUACCCAUUCCAGAAAUGGGUCAGAAUGGACAAAAGAAAUACCAGAUCAAUCUAAAGAGUCAUUCAGGACCUAUCCAUGUGCUGCUUAUAAAUAAAGAGUCGAGUUCAUCUAAGCCCGUGGUUUUUCCUGUUCCCCCACCUGAUGACCUCACACAGCCUUCCUCCCAGUCCUUGACUCCAGUGACUCCACAGAAAUCCAGCAUGGCAACUCAAAAUCUGCCUGAGCAACAUGUCUCUGAAAGAAGCCAGGCUCUGCAGCAGACAUCAGCUACAGAUAUAUCUUCAGCAGGAUCUAUUAGUGGAGAUAUCAUUGAUGAGUUAAUGUCUUCUGACGUGUUUCCUCUCUUAAGGCUUUCUCCUACCCCGGCAGAUGACUACAACUUUAAUUUAGAUGAUAACGAAGGAGUUUGUGAUCUGUUUGAUGUCCAGAUACUAAAUUAUUAGAUUCCAUGGAAACUUGGGACUGUUAUCUACCUCUAACUGUGUAACAUUUUAGACUUCUUAAUAACCUAAAUAUUUAAAAUAAUGAAUGUAACACCUUUUUUAGUUCACUGAUUCUGAAGUGUUCUUCCCUAAUACUUUCUUUACUUCACAAAACUUCAACCAUAAAAACAAAGGGCUCUGAUUGCUUUAGGGGAUAAGUGAUUUAAUAUCCACAAACGUCCCCACUCCCAAAAGUAACUAUAUUCUGGAUUUCAACUUUUCUUCUAAUUGUGAAUCCUUCUGUUUUUUCUUCUUAAGGAGGAAAGUUAAAGGACACUACAGGUCAUCAAAAACAAGUUGGCCAAGGACUCAUUACUUGUCUUAUAUUUUUACUGCCACUAAACUGCCUGUAUUUCUGUAUGUCCUUCUAUCCAAACAGACGUUCACUGCCACUUGUAAAGUGAAGGAUGUAAACGAGGAUAUAUAACUGUUUCAGUGAACAGAUUUUGUGAAGUGCCUUCUGUUUUAGCACUUUAAGUUUAUCACAUUUUGUUGACUUCUGACAUUCCACUUUCCUAGGUUAUAGGAAAGAUCUGUUUAUGUAGUUUGUUUUUAAAAUGUGCCAAUGCCUGUACAUUAACAAGAUUUUUAAAAAUAAAAUUGUAUAAAACAUUCAA